GCUGGAGGCGCCAUUGGAGCCGGCUUGGCUGGCGAGCCCGGCUGAGGAGCCUCUUGGGCCGCACUUACCGCCGCGUCCGCUCCCGGUCCCUGGCCCCUCAGCGGCAUGGCGUGCGGGGCGACGCUGAAGCGGCCCAUGGAGUUCGAGGCGGCGCUGCUGAGCCCCGGCUCCCCGAAGCGGCGGCGCUGCGCCCCUCUGCCCGGCCCCACUCCGGGCCUCAGGCCCCCGGACGCCGAGCCGCCGCCGCCGUUUCAGACGCAGACCCCACCGCAGAGUCUGCAGCAGCCCGCCCCGCCCGGCAGCGAGCGGCGCCUUCCAACUCCGGAGCAAAUUUUUCAGAACAUAAAACAAGAAUAUAGUCGUUAUCAGAGGUGGAGACAUUUAGAAGUUGUUCUUAAUCAGAGUGAAGCUUGUGCUUCGGAAAGUCAACCUCACUCCUCAGCACUCACAGCACCUAGCUCUCCAGGUUCCUCAUGGAUGAAGAAGGACCAGCCCACAUUUACCCUCCGACAAGUUGGCAUAAUAUGUGAGCGCCUCUUAAAAGACUAUGAAGAUAAAAUUCGGGAGGAGUAUGAGCAAAUCCUCAAUACCAAACUAGCAGAACAAUAUGAAUCUUUUGUGAAAUUCACACAUGAUCAGAUUAUGCGACGGUAUGGGACAAGGCCAACAAGCUAUGUGUCAUGAAGCUUUGUCACAUAUCUGGGUACCAGGUUUGACCUCAAGAGAUGGCUGCUGUACACUUUUUGCAACUGGUUUGAUGUCACAUUUCAGCUCCAACUUUGCAUCCUGAGAACACUUAAACGUUUCUGCAGGUCCAUUUUAUACAACUUGAAAGACCGUAAAACUUUCUGGUUGCCACAAGCAUAUCUUUCUUUUCUGCUCAUCCAAUAAACAGCUGUGCCCUACUGUGAUAGAUUUUCCAAACAAAAAUACCUGGAGCAGCAGUUUAGCAAAAUAUGCCUUCAGUGGCAUUCAACAAAUGGAGUUUCCCCAAGCACAGUUCUGUAAGAAGUGCGUGUGAGAGUGUGUGUAUAUGUGUGUAUGUGUAUUUUAAGUUAUUAUUUGUAUUGUGCAAAAAUUUUUUUUUGAUCUUGGGGAUUCUGGCUGUGAAUUUGGUGCACGACAAUUAUGGUAAAAAAACAUUUGCUUGGUCUAAAGAAGAUCAUUAAUGUUUUGUGACCAUACAAGUUGUAACAGUGGAUUGUUUUUAUGUGUAGGUAUUGUUAAAUACAGGGACUGUUUCCAGGCACAGAAUAUGAAUCGUAAGUUAGGAUGGACAUUAGAUGUGAUUAUGAUGAUAAAGCGAAGGUCUGCGGUCCUAUAUCUACAGACACGUGGUGAGAAAUUAGAACAAACUGGAGACGGGCCAUUGACACAUGGACUCUGCCUGGGCAUGUUAGGUUAAUUCUUUGACUCCAAGCCUUAAAAUACUCACAUGGAGUCAGCGCUCACCUCAUUCACACAAUUAUCAUAGAGCUCCCUGGACACUGAACCUCUAAAGGGAAAAGGUCUACCCUGGAGCCAGGAGCAUCAGGGUUGGCUUGGGAGCAUGAGAGGUGAGCCCAGGGCUAGGCCUGGGCCAGGCCCCGGCAGCACUGCUACUUGGGAGGAGCCACUUCACCUUUGUAUUAGUUAUUAAAAAAUAUAAUUUGGGCUGGGCGCAGUGGCUCACGCCUGUAAUCCCAGCACUUUGGGAGUCCGAGGCAUGCGGAUCACUUGAGGUCAGGAGUUCGAGACCACCCUGGCCAAUAUGGUGAAACCCCAUCUCUACUAAAAAUACAACAAAGUUAGCCGGGCGUGGUGGCAGGCGUCUGUAAUCCCAGCUGCUUGGGAGGCUGAGGCAGGAGAAUCACUUGAACCCUGGAGGUGGCGGUUGCAGUGAGCACAGAUCAUGCCACUGCACUCCAGCCUGGGCAACAAAACGAGACUUCGUCUCAAAAAAAAAAAAAAAACAUAGAAUUUGGAUCCUUUGGUCGGGUUCUCCCAAAUUCUUUUGAGGUGUCCAUGGUCAACUGCUUCAGCUUUGUUUUGGCAACCCCCUGCCCGAAGUCGCAUAUAGGCUGUUCUUCACCUUGUUUCCAAGGCUGAGGAACAGAAAGUAGCCUCUGUUUUGAGGAGGUGGAAGUUAAGUAUACAUUUAUUUUUUACUGUGACUUGUUCAGGACCACAUUUUACAAAAUGCCUUGUUUCCUUCAUUGUUUCUGGAAAGGAAAGUUCUAUUAAUAUUGUUUUACUUUGAAUAUAGAAUAGUUUUUUUAAUUAGGGCUUAUUUUGAAAAAUUCUGAGUUUAAUUCAAAUGUAUGCCAAUACCUUCCAAAGUAAGGUAAUAUUCAGAGACAGUUGUUGUGAUCAGAUGGCUUAGAGAAAUUUCUGGAAUAUUCACAUUCGAAGAUUCCUUAUUAAUGAAUGUCUUUGACUUAAAUCUAACCAAAAACUGCAACAUUAUUCUUUGUACAUUUUCAUUAUAUAGUGUUAACAAGCUUAGUUGCAAACAAAUAAAAUACUUAAGCUAUUUGUUUACCUUGCCUUCUUAAUACUGUGAUAAUGUUUAUUAAUUCAAAUAACUUAUGUGAGAGCUGCUAUAACCAUUUCCCCAGUUCAACAUUGCAUUGAAAAUUUAUGGACCUUUAAAAAAAAAAGCCCAACAGUGAUUUUUUUUUAAUAAUUAAAGAAUGAUUUUACUUUGUA